GAGGAAACGCGCUCUUAGACCAUGGCGACCCAGGCGAAGCGUCCACGGGUGGCGGGGCCCGUGGACGGCGGCGACCUGGAUCCUGUGGCCUGCUUCCUGAGCUGGUGCCGGCGGGUGGGGCUGGAGCUGAGUCCCAAGGUGAGCGAGCGAGCCGGCGGGCGGAGGACCCGCGGCGGGGCGCGGGCUGCCCUGACCAGCCCUCCUGCUCAGGUGGCGGUCAGCCGGCAGGGCACGGUGGCCGGCUACGGCAUGGUGGCCCGGGAGAGCGUGCAGGCCGGAGAGCUGUUGUUCGUGGUGCCGCGGGCCGCGCUCCUGUCGCAGCACACCUGCUCCAUCGGCGGCCUGCUGGAGCGAGAGCGAGUUGCGCUGCAGAGCCAGUCGGGCUGGGUGCCACUGCUGCUGGCGCUGCUCCACGAGCUGCAGGCCCCGGCCUCACGCUGGAGGCCCUACUUUGCGCUCUGGCCCGAGCUGGGCCGCUUGGAGCACCCGAUGUUCUGGCCAGAGGAGGAGCGCCGGUGCCUGCUCCAGGGCACAGGCGUACCUGAGGCCGUGGAGAAGGAUUUGGCCAACAUCCGCAGCGAGUACCAGUCCAUCGUGCUGCCCUUCAUGGAAGCCCACCCCGAUCUCUUCAGCCUCAGGGUUCGCUCCCUAGAACUCUACCACCAGCUGGUGGCCCUUGUGAUGGCCUAUAGCUUUCAGGAACCACUGGAGGAAGAAGAGGAUGAAAAGGAGCCCAACUCCCCCGUGAUGGUGCCUGCUGCAGACAUACUAAACCACUUAGCCAAUCACAACGCCAAUCUAGAAUACUCUGCGAAUUGUCUUCGGAUGGUAGCCACUCAGCCCAUUCCUAAAGGCCAUGAGAUUUUCAACACUUAUGGGCAAAUGGCUAACUGGCAACUGAUUCAUAUGUACGGUUUUGUUGAACCAUAUCCUGACAACACAGAUGACACAGCUGACAUUCAGAUGGUGACAGUUCGUGAGGCAGCAUUACAGGGAACAAAAACUGAAGCUGAAAGGCACCUAGUGUACGAGCGCUGGGAUUUCCUAUGCAAACUGGAGAUGGUAGGGGAAGAGGGAGCCUUUGUGAUAGGGAGGGAGGAGGUGCUGACUGAAGAGGAGCUGACCACCACACUAAAGGUACUGUGCAUGCCUGCUGAGGAGUUCAGAGAGCUUAAAGACCAGGAUGGAGGGGGAGAUGAUAAAAGGGAAGAGGGCAGCCUGACGAUCACAAAUAUUCCCAAGCUCAAAGCAUCGUGGAGACAGCUGCUUCAAAACAGUGUUCUACUGACUUUGCAGACCUAUGCCACAGACUUAAAAACUGACCAAGGUUUACUCAGUAAUAAGGAAGUCUAUGCGAAACUCAGCUGGAGGGAACAGCAAGCCUUACAGGUUCGCUAUGGUCAGAAGAUGAUCUUACAUCAGUUGUUGGAGCUGACAAGUUAGCAGUUUCCCUGUUCCCUGAAGGAACAGCAAUAAGAACUUUAUUCUAAGCUAAUACUCAUUGAUGUUUGAAAAAGAGGAAAAUUUGGAUCUUUCUUUUGCUUACUAAACACCAAGAGGAAAAGUAGCAAAGUUGGUGUGCUAGGAUUAACUCAGGUAAGGGUGAUGUGUUUUAGGAUUGAGAACAGCAGACUUGGGAAUCACUGCUAAUUGUUACUUAAAGCAUGUUACAGAUGUUUUGUUCUCAGUUUUAACCAAAGCCAGUGGACAUACGGUAGUAAUAAGUAAGUCUUGUUGUGUUUCAGCAUUUAAUAAUAGACUUUGGAGGUAGACCCCUGGUUUAAAUCUAAGUCUAGUUUGAGGAAGUCACUUAACCUUUAUUGAAAAGACUCUGGAUUUAAUAAGCUGUGUAACUGGUACUCGAUAGUUACCCAAAGUUCAGUCUAGAUGGCACAAACCACCUCUCAGGGAAUAAACCCUAAGACAUCACUCAAGGAGGACUUCAAUUAUUUAAUUUUGAACUGUUUUGUCCUCUCUGGCCAUAAAACUUGACAGUCAUGAAAGGUAAGGCAAAUUUUAAGUGGGUUAAGUUUUUAAAUACGUAUCUACUCAUUUUCUUUAAAAAAAAAAAAAAAAUACCUGGGGGAAAAGGAUAUUAAAACUGGGUAUUUUAAACUCAGCUUAACCAGAUAAACCUGCUCCAGCAUUUGUCCAGUGUUGAAAUAAAUAGGAAGAAAAAUACAAUUUCCUUAAACAUGCCAGCUUAGUAGUAGGAAUGACCUAUCAAUCAAUCAAUCAAUCAUUCAGCAAGAAGUUAGUUGGUGGUUCCCCAUGGCCCCAAGGUCUGCAGGGCUGGAUUGUCCACUUUUCCUCCUCACCACCAGCACUGGCUGCUGCUACUGAGAAAGGCACAGUGGACUCAUGUGUGUGUCAUGACUUUAAUGGUUAGCUACAGUAUGCAUACACAUACAAGAAGUAGGGGAGCUGAAGCCCAGGAAAAGGCUACAAAAUACAACACAGGGACCAAUACAUUUGCAAAACAUUCAAAAUCCUUAUAAAAGGGGCUGUAUUGGUCCUUUCAACUUUGUCAUUAUUCAGCUUAGCCUGUAUGGCCAUUCAUUCAGUGGGGUAAUGGGGGAGAACAAUUAAUUAAUGAGAUUUGGUUCCCUUUCCUAUAUUCCCACUGUUUUUAAGUUUCAGGAGAGGAUUGGGGGGGUGAGGGUAGGGGUGGGCUUUAGGCCUGGUCUGGUUUCCCUUUAUAUAAAGAGCUGACCCCCAUCUCAGGCGGCUGAGGUGUAUAAUCCCCAAAAGAAAUAAGAUGGUACAAAUGCAGUCAGCUUUGGAAUACGUUUGGGUAGAGACAAAAUGGAAACUCAUGGGAUUCCAAUAGUGAGCCCUUCCCAUGUUCCUGGACAUAUCCAAUUCUAGCACAUCCACAUUUUUAAUAACUUAGUGAUUUUCAAGGUCCCCUGUCCACAUUAAAAAAAUAAGUUACAUAAUAUUCAAACUGGCUUUUUGCUAUUCUUUGGGACACCAGGAAUGUCAGAAGACAUGGAGCUAUGCCCUCAGACAAGUGCAUGGCAUCAGCUGCCUCUUCAUUACAAGGUACCAGUUUAUGUACUUGCCUUGGACACAGCUUGCACAAAGCCAAGAAGUUCCAGACAAAGGUUUUCUCUUUCAUGUAUUUACACAAGUUCAAAAUGAUAUUCACAGCAUCUUCUAAAUUUUGGCCAAGAGUCAAAAAAAUGCAUUUAAACUUUGGAACGUGCCCACAUAAGACAGGAGGCUGAUCCCAACAGUAGUUGGGGCAGAUACCCACAAACCAAAGGGCUGGGAAAGUCAGGAAGAGCUGAAAGGAUUCUUCAGUCAGUUUAUGAACUCGGUGCAGUGAGACCUCUAGACUGACACGUACAACAGAGAUGCAGUUUCGUCUAACUGGCACCUGUCCCUUCCAUUACUUGCUGGGCCUGCUUCUGUCCCAUGCAGCACUGUGCGACCGACUGGAAUAACCUGAAGGAUGAAGACAGUUACAAAUCUCUGAUUAAAGAGUAGGCCUAACAAUACCUUGCAUCUCAUUCAGCUGACCCAACCUAGAGACAGAUGGUUUUCAGUCUCCAGUCUCAUUCCUAGACAAUUAAAAAUUACUUUGAACUCACUUUUCGAUUUCUGGGGCACAGUGUACAAAUUCAUGGUUCCAGAACUUAAACGCUGGGUUUUUAAUCAGCUCAAUGAAGGUAAUAAGAAGACCCCAAGGAUGUGGCCUAUUUACAAUCAACCGUUCCAAGAGAACUCUGGAAAAAGGGAGAAAGAGCUAGUUAAUGUAUAGAAGCAUACAAAUUCAUGAUUAUUCUUCCAUUACUUUUUUUCUAACUUCUCCCUGACUAUUGAACCACAUGCAAAAGUUUUCACCUUUAGUAAAGACAGGUGGAUUAAUAUACUCCAAAUAGCACAGGUUGGAAUACCUGGGUUUGAACCCUGCUCUUAGCCGUAGAAGACUAAGUAUUUAUAUAAAGUGCAGAUAAUGGUAUCUACCUCACAGCUGUUCAGAAUAAGGGGUGAUGGGGGAGAGGAAGCCACAUAAAGCCCAGAGUACAUGGCACACAAAGUUAGUACAAAAAGUAGUAAUUUCCAGAAUGAGCUCCCAGGCCGGGCACAGUGGCUCAUGCCUGUAAUCCAGCACUUUGGGAGGCCGAGGCAGGUGGAUCACCUGAGGUCAGGAGUUCGAGACCAGCCUGGCCAACAUGGUGAAACCCCAUCUCUGCUACAAAUAUAAAAAUUAGUCAGACAUGGUGGCCACAUGCCUGUAAUCCCAGCAGUCGGACGCUGAGGCAGGAGAAUCGCUUGAACCCAGUAGGUGGAGGUUGUGGUGAGCCGAGAUGGUGCCACUGCACUCCAGCCUGGGAGACAGAGUGAGACCCUGUCUCAAAUAAACAGAUAAAUUAAAUAAAUAAAUAAGCUCACUCUCAAUAAAAAGGAAACAGAAAAUAAGAAUUAAGUAUUCUAACACUGCAGGCUGGGCACAGUGACUCACGCCUGUAAUCCCAGCACUCUGGGAGGCCAAGACGGGUGGAUCACGAGGUCGGGAGUUCAAGACCAGCCUGGCCAAGAUGGUGAAACCCCGUCUCUACUAAAAAUACAAAAAAUUAGCCGGACGUGGUGGCAGGUGCCUGUAAUCCCAGCUACUCAGGAGGCGACAAAGCGAGACUGUCUCAAAAAAAAAAAAAAAAAAAAAAAAAAAAAAGCUAACAUUGCUAGUUCACAUGUAAAUUGGUAAAAUUUUUCCGAAUGCCAGUAAGCAUUGGCUUAACUUUAUAUCCUUUCACGUACCAACUGUACAUGAAGCAUAACAAAGAUUACAAGUCCAAGGAGACUUACUGCAGCUUUAUAUAAACAAAAUGGAUCAUCAUCAUCUAAGCAUCCAAUAAGAUAUUAAAUUUUAGUACACAAAUCAAAGGAAUACCAUAUUUAGCACCAUAGGUGACUAAUUAGGCAAAUGAGCAAGUUUUAAGAGUCUGGCCCAAUUUUUAAAGUGUGUGUGUGUGUGUAUCACAAUCUCUCUAAUGCUAUAUGUAGUCUAGGCAAUCUGGCAACAGAUUCCUAACUAUUGUUAGGAAAAUGCAAGUAUGAUCCUGUUAUUGCUACUGCUUUCAACCCAGAGGUAAUGAGGAAAAGUCCAAGUUCCUUAACAUAGACUUCAUAGGCCUGCAUGAUUUAGGACUGGUUAUCACCACCACCUCAGAGAAACUCCUGACCUUUAAUCAAAAUGUGCCUUGUGGUAAACUACUUUUCAUUUAAGCCAUGAUUGCGAUUUAUAAUUCCCUAUCUUGUGAUAAAUGUCCAUCAGAAUGAGUAUUAAGAGGGCAGGAACCAUCCAUUUUGCUCACAAUUGUAUCCCACAUUUAACACAUUAUUGGACAUGUAAAAGAUUUUCACUGAAGGCCGGGUGCAGUGGCUCACGCCUGUAAUCCCAGCACUUUGGGAGGCUGAGGCGGGUGGAUCACUUGAGGUCAGGAGUUCAAGAUCAGCCUGGCCAACAUGGUGAAACCCCGUCUCUACUAAAAUACAAAAAUUAGCUGGGCGUGGUGGCAGGCGCCUGUAAUCCCAGCUACUUGAGAGGCUAAGGCACGAGAAUCGCUUGAACCUGGGAGGCGGAGGUUGCAGUGAGCCAAGAUGGCGCCACUGUACUGCAGACUGAGUGACAGAGCAACACUCCGUCUCAAAAAAACAAAAAAAAAACCAACCAAACGGAUUUUCACUGAACACUGAAAGCAUAAAGAGGAAAAAAAAAAGAUGAAAGGGAGGAGAUCCUUUUGAAGCAUUUAAAAAAUAAGCUGCUCGCUUACCUUGUGAUCUGUUCUUGGAUGGCUUCCGUAUUGGCCUCUGCAAAAAGGUACAGCAUGGUGCAACUGAAGUAGUGAGUGUGGCUAUUUGGGUACCGGAGCUGAUUUGCAAUUGCAUUCAAAAAGAGAUAGCGACCUAGAAAUUAAGAAACCUUGACUUAGGACUUAGUCUGAAAGGCCAACAUGGGAAGACAGUUCUAACUGGCUAGGGUUUGGGUUUCUGACAGAGGCUUUCAAAUUAAUCUUUGGUUUAAAGCAGUGGUUCUUGGGACCCCAAAGAGUUCUCAUUUCUGUGCGUUUUAUUUCAGAAUUUUCCACAUUAGAAAUUAGAUUUUAAAAAUAUUCAUUUUUAAAAACAGACCCACUAUGUGCUAAUGUAAGAAACAUGAACUAUUUUCUGGUGACACUCAUCACUAAGUCUUUCUACAUUUUGCAGAUCUCUAAGUCUUGCUUAAUAAAAGACAGCUGGAUUCUCA